GUUGUUGCGGCUUCCGCCGCGGGUGGAAGAAGAUGGCGUCGGGUGGUGGUGGCUGUAGCGCUUCGGAGAGACUGCCUCCGCCCUUCCCCGGCCUGGAGCCGGAGUCCGAGGGGGCGGCCGGGGGAUCAGAACCCGAGGCUGGGGACAGCGACACCGAGGGGGAGGACAUUUUCACCGGCGCCGCGGUGGUCAGUAAACAUCAGUCUCCAAAGAUAACUACAUCCCUUCUUCCCAUCAACAAUGGCUCCAAAGAAAAUGGGAUCCAUGAAGAACAAGACCAAGAGCCACAGGAUCUCUUUGCAGAUGCCACAGUGGAGCUAUCCUUGGACAGCACACAAAAUAAUCAGAAGAAGGUGCUAGCCAAAACACUCAUUUCUCUUCCUCCUCAGGAAGCCACAAAUUCUUCGAAGCCCCAGCCAACCUAUGAGGAGCUAGAGGAAGAAGAACAGGAGGAUCAAUUUGAUUUGACAGUCGGUAUAACUGAUCCUGAGAAGAUAGGGGAUGGUAUGAAUGCAUAUGUAGCCUACAAAGUUACAACACAGACAAGCUUACCAUUGUUCAGAAGCAAACAGUUUGCAGUAAAAAGAAGAUUUAGUGACUUUCUGGGUCUUUAUGAGAAGCUUUCCGAGAAGCACUCUCAGAAUGGCUUCAUUGUCCCUCCGCCCCCGGAGAAGAGCCUCAUAGGGAUGACAAAAGUGAAAGUUGGGAAGGAAGAUUCUUCUUCUGCAGAAUUUCUUGAAAAACGGAGGGCCGCUUUAGAAAGGUACCUUCAGAGGAUUGUAAAUCAUCCUACCAUGUUACAGGACCCUGACGUCAGAGAGUUCUUGGAAAAAGAAGAGCUGCCACGUGCCGUGGGUACCCAGACAUUGAGUGGUGCUGGUCUCCUCAAGAUGUUCAACAAAGCCACAGAUGCCGUCAGCAAAAUGACCAUCAAGAUGAAUGAAUCAGACAUUUGGUUUGAGGAGAAGCUCCAGGAGGUAGAGUGUGAGGAGCAGCGCUUACGGAAACUGCAUGCUGUUGUAGAAACUCUAGUCAACCAUAGGAAAGAGCUAGCGCUGAACACAGCCCAGUUUGCAAAGAGUCUAGCCAUGCUUGGGAGCUCUGAGGACAACACGGCAUUGUCACGGGCACUCUCCCAGCUGGCUGAGGUGGAAGAAAAAAUUGAGCAGCUCCACCAGGAACAGGCCAACAAUGACUUCUUCCUCCUUGCUGAGCUCCUGAGUGACUACAUUCGCCUCCUGGCCAUAGUCCGCGCUGCCUUCGACCAGCGCAUGAAGACAUGGCAGCGCUGGCAGGAUGCCCAAGCCACACUGCAGAAGAAGCGGGAGGCCGAGGCUCGGCUGCUGUGGGCCAACAAGCCUGAUAAGCUGCAGCAGGCCAAGGACGAGAUCCUCGAGUGGGAGUCUCGGGUGACUCAAUAUGAAAGGGACUUCGAGAGGAUUUCAACAGUGGUCCGAAAAGAAGUGAUACGGUUUGAGAAAGAGAAAUCCAAGGACUUCAAGAACCACGUGAUCAAGUACCUUGAGACACUCCUUUACUCACAGCAGCAGCUGGCAAAGUACUGGGAAGCCUUCCUUCCUGAGGCAAAGGCCAUCUCCUAAUGGACCAAGGACCCCAGAGCCCACCUGUGUGACGCUGCCUUUUUAUACACUGUCCUCCUCCACCUUGAUGGACCCCUAGUGAUGCAUCCUGCCUAGGCUGGACUUAACCCCUUCCUCCCUGUCCCCACGACCAACUGUCCCCAGUUACUCUAACCGUUAUUUCAUUUAGCUUCCAUAUAUAUUUUCUUACCUAAGAGAAUAGUUUCCUGCUUUAAGCAAAAGACCUACAAUAGGUGGUGGAAUUAUGGGAUGGGGUGGAGUAUUGAUAUAAAUAUAUAAAUACAAAUGUAUAUUUUUCAGGAUGUGGUUUAGGAACUGGGAAUAACGUUUUCUGUUACUCCUGAUGGUGCCAUGAAAAGGUUAUGUAAUAAAAUAUUUUAAAAUCAGGUCACAUGACUCAGAAUGUUGGUGGUUUUUGCUUAGGCUGGGGAGCAGUUGGGAAUCAGGUCUGGAAUACUCCUAACCAAGAAGUUGCCCAGGUAUAGUAAGUUUUUCUCUACCGUUCACAAGUUUUGUGCUGCUGCUUCCCUCUGGAAAUGGGGUUUCUUUCUCUCCGCCUACCUCAGCUACCUGUUCUGAGGGUCUCAAUCUGUUUCGUAUUCCCACUUCUUUAGGGAAGGAGUUUUAAAAACAUCUCUUAAAAUAAGAGGAGCAAAAUCUAUUAAAACCUAUUCUCCUGCAAAGGAGGCAGAGACUUUCUCUCUCUCUUUUUUUUUUUUUUUUGGUGUCCCUAUCAUUAAGCAAGAGCCUUUCUCUUUUAUUCUUCCUGCUUCCCUAAGCUGCUCAGGGUUCUCUGAGUCUUGCCCUCUGAUGGCAAGUCUUAUAUAUAACUAAACCUAUUUUUGUCACCCAUCAAAACACAUCCUCAGUAGACUGUGUGAAGGUGUGAAGGUCUGAUAAUGACUUGAUGCUUUGUCUCCAUAGACAUGAAAGCCAUGCCCUCUGCCUCUAGAUAGGGUGAUCCAAGAGCUCCUGAACCUUAGGAGGUUCAAAGAAGCUCUACUGUCUGUGCCCAGGAGGUAGCCUGCCAGCAAGAGCCCUCAGGAGUUGCACACACAGCCAAAGGGUGUUCACACAGAUCUCUGCCGGUCUAGCCAGGGGAGGCCAGAGUCUCGUCAGUCAAGGAUGGGCUUCCCCCUUAGCUGUGUCCACAGCUGCUCAAGCUAUACUGGUCAGAGUGGGCUUUGAAGCUCCUUUGUGAGCUCGAGCUGCUGACUGCCACUAUGGGAGCCUUGCCACCUCCAGCCCCUCCAUCCCAAAGACGCUCCUGCCACUGGGGCCCCAGGUCCUGCUGUAUCAGUUCUCUUUGGUGGGGGGCUAAGGUUUGGGGCGAGGCAACCUGAGACAAGAAAACGCAGUAAACAUUCUGAUUCCCUGUACACAGAUGCAGCACCAGGGGAAGGGCCAGUGGUGCAAGUAUUUCUUUUUAACAGGUGAAGUUUUUGGAAAAAGUCACUCUCCCUACCCCUCAGUAUCCUUACCAUCAACUUUGGUUUUAUCCUUCCAGUCUUUAUUAUAUGCUUGCUUUUACAUAGUUGUAAUAAUAUACACAUAAAGUAUUUUGUAUCCUGCUUUUAUCAUUCAACAUUGUACAUGUUAUAAGCAUUUUACUAUAUUGUUAUAUAUCUUCACAAAGUUGAUCUGUAAAGCUGUGUAAUUUGAAGGCAUCCAUAGGGUGACUGUACCAUAAUUUUGAUUCAUCCCUUGUUGUUGGAUUCUUGGUCAGGGGUUGUUUGUUUUGUUUUAUUGGUAACUUUAAAAUUUUGAAUACAAUUUCAGAUUUACAGAAAAGUUGCAGGAAUAUCACAAAGAACUCCUAUAUAUCUUUUAUCCAGAUUUACUGAGUGUUUACAUUUUAUCCCAUUUGCCUUAUCUAUAUUUCAUGUUGCAUUUUCUUAAUCAUUUGAGAAUAAUUUGCACAGAUACCCCAUUAUGCCCAAAACAGUAUGCAUUUCCCUAAGAACAGGACAUUCUCUUCUAAGAGAAGAAGAGAAUUACUUUAAGCAUUAUUCAGUAUUUUUUUAAGUAUUAUUAUCAAAAUCAGGAAGUUUAACAGUGAUUUAAUACUGUUAUCUAACCCAUGAUUCAUAUUUAAAUUUUGCCAUUUAUCCCAAUAAUGUCCUUUGUAGCCAUUCUUUUACCUUGUGCAGGAUCAUGUUACAUUUGUAAACGUGUGUCUCUCAAUACUGCAGAUUCCUCAACUUUCUUUUGUCUUUCAUUACCAUGACAUUUUUGAAGAAUACAGGCUAUUUUGUCGAAUGUUCCUCAGUUUGGAUUUGUGUGAUGGUUCCGCAUGACUAGGUGAGGGUUUUGCAUUCUGGGUGGGAAUAUCACAGAAGCAGUGUGUCGUCAGUGCGUCGUAAUCAGCAUAUAAUGUCAGUUGGUCCCAUUAAUGUUGUUAACUCUGUUCACCGCUUAGGUUGGUGUCUGCCAGAUUUCAUUUUAAAUUUACGAUUUCCUCUUUGUAAUUUACAAGUAAUUUGUGGGGAGAUACUUUGAGACUAUAUAAGUAUUUUGUUCCUCAUUCACCAGUUAUAUAGUAUCAGUUGAUUAGUCUUGUCCCAGUUAUUACUGUCAUGAUUGACCAACAUGAUUUCCUAACUCCAUAAUGCCUUCUACAUUUAUUGGUUGACAUUCUACAUACAAAGAAAAACAUCCUUUCUCACCAUUUAUUUAUUCACUUGUUUAUCAAUAUGGAUGCAGGGAUUCCUGUUUUACUCAGAGUUGCAAGCCAUUGCUUUGAUUUUAUCUUGAUUCUCAAAUUGUCCCAGAUUUAUAGCGGCCUCUUGUGUGUUUGUAGCUUGCUCCCAUCAUGUUUUGAGUACUUUCUUACCUUCUGGCAUAACAAGAUGUUCCAGGCUCAUCUUGAAUGUUCCCUACCCUAGCCCUGGAAUCAGCCAUUUCUCCAGGGAGUCUUGGUUCCUUAUAAUGGAGAAUGGUAUUUAUUUAUUUUUAUUUGAUUUGAUUAUUAUUACUAUUUUUGAGACAGAGUCUCGCUCUUGUCGCCCAGGCUGGAUUGCAAUGGCACAAUCUCAGCUCACUGCAACCUCCACCUACCAGGUUCAAGCAAUUCUCCUGCCUCAGCCUUCCAAGUAGCUGGGAUUACAGGUGCCUGCCCCCACACCCAGCUAAUUUUUGCAUUUUUGGUAGAAAUGGGGGUUUUACCAUGUUGGGGAGGCUGGUCUCGAACUCCUGACCUCAGGUGAUCUGCCCACCUCAACCUCCCAAAGUGCUGGGAUUACAGGUGUGAGCCACCAUACCCAGCCAGAGAAUGUUAUUUAGAAACCAAGAUCUGGGUGCCAAAUGUGCUGCUUGUUACUGGAAUGUCAUUGCCUCUAGGCUCUCACCAUACAGUGCAAAGAGAUGAUAGAUAGAUAGAUAGAUAGAUAGAUAGAUAGAUAGAUAGAUGAUAGAUAUAGAUAGAUAGAUAGAUUGAUUGAUUUGUAGAAACAAGAUAGGUUAGAGAUACCUGACAUAAAUAGAUACUAAAAAUCAUGAAUUCACACUGAUGCUUUGAGACCAGCCCUGUAGGUUUAUUCCAGUCUGCCCCCUUUUCCAUGUUGUUAACUCUUUCCUCCAGAGAGACAAAGAUUUCAGGUUGCUUUGUUAAGUUCCAUCUAAUGAUCAUUCUGACGUAAGUCUGUUUUUCUUAUUUCCUUGGAAUGAUGUCUCCUCUGGUUUCAGAACUUCCUCCUCUGCUUCCUGUAUCCUGAGGCUGGCGGGGCCAGUUGUCUUUAGGGCUUGUGCAUUUUUGUAAAGAGCUUGCACGUGUGGAAAUCAAGUAGGCCAGUAGUGGGUUAGGGGUACUGAGCCAGAAGCCUCUACAAGGAAUAACAGGAGCACAAAGGAAGAAGGUGGUAUUCCAGCUGGGGACCCAGGAGGGAGGACUUUGUGGAGAACCUGAUGCUUGAACUGAGUCUAAAAGGUGUAAAAGUGUUUGUUGCUUCUGCCUCCCUGUCUGUCUGGCAGGGUGAGGUAGGCGCAUCUAGGGAAAUGUCAAGUGGCUUGGUGUAGGGUAAAGUCAGUGAGGCCCAUGGAGAAAAACGAGCAGGAGCCACAUCACAUGGGUGUCUGAUAGGACCUGGGAGGCGCUUUCCACAUUACCAUUGUCGCUUCGUGAUCUGGACACACCAGAAGGCGUGAGACUGGAGGCAGGAAGAGCAGCCAGGCUUAUCCCUACCCUCAGGAGAGCUGAAAAGGGCAGGUAUGGUGGGGCCAGAGCUCAGGAGAGUUUCGGAACCACUGAGAUCGGUCCUUGAUUUGAUGAGAGGCUUGAGGGGAGAGGGAGGUAGCUAGGAUGCCCCGCAAGCUUCUGGCCCAGACACUGGGCAGACAAUGAAACCCUUUGUAACACAUGAGGCAAUAGGUUUGGGGCAGAUGGGAGGGGAAGCAGUGGUGGGGGCAGUGAGUGCUGAAGGUGUUUUAAGAAGCGGCUCUGGGCCAGGCACAGUGGCUUAUGCCUGUAUUCCUAGCAUUUUGGGAGGCCGAGGUGGGAGAAUCACUUGAGCCCAAGAAUUUGAGACCAGCCUGGGGAAUAUAGUGAGACCCUGUCCCUACAAAAAUAAAAACAACUAGCUGGGUGUGUGGUGGUGCAUGCCUGUAGGCCCAGCUACGCGGGAACAUCACCUGAGCCCAGGAGGUUGAGGUUGCAGUGAGCUACAGUUGCGCCACUGCACUCCAGCCUAGGUGACAGAGCAAGAUCUUGUCUCAAAAAAAAAAGCAGCUCUGGAUGGGAAGGGAGGCCAGUUGCUUUAAGUAGGGGAGAUAGAGUUAAAGGAGGCUUUGUUUUAUUUAAAGGUGGGACAAACUUAAGCAUGUUAAUAAAAUUCAGAGAAGAGAAAGAGAAUGACUAUCAGAGCCAUGUUUGGAAGAAAAUGGGGUCCAGAGCACAGGAAGGGGACCUGUGUUCAGAGGGUGCCUCACUGCUGAGGCCACAGGAAAGAAUCUGUAGGUGGAGGGGAGGCCGAAGAGGGGAAGUUUCAUGCUUGAUAAUUAAAAUUUUCUGAGAUAGGAAUGUCAUAUUUACCUAUUUAAGCCAAGUUUUUUUAGAUAAAAGGUAUGGAACCUGCUUUCCCCUUGGCUAGUUCAGCGUUUGGGCUCCGGAGUGCUGAAGAUGAGGACUGGACUUCGAGCUGGUGUGAUCCCAGUAUUCAGUGUCAGUACUCAGUGACAAAAUAAAUGAGAGAAACGGGAAUAAGAAUUGUCGCCUACACAAAAAUACCAGCAACUGUUAACUCUUCCCAGAAGAUUUUCAUUCUGAAUGCUCCUGUAGCUAGGAACCCUAAAAAGUCUUUGAAGCAACUCAAGUUUUAAAAAAGGGGAGGAACUCCUGGAAAUCUCAGGAUGGGGCCAAGAUGUGGCUGGAGAGUGUGUGGUGAUGGAGGGCGUGUCUUUUGCCGAGCACACUCAGGGCCCACGGGAAGCCCAUAGACUUCAAGGACAUCAAGCCCCAAGGUGGUGGGAUUUUCCCCACCAGUACUUGGCAGCCUAGGGGGAAGGGGAGGGCGGGAGAAGAUAAUGGGGAUCCCUGGCUCCAAACAUAGGAGGACACAUCUGUGCUACAGUGCGCACAUGCCUGGAUGUACACUCUGUCUUUGGAGACACUGGCUAAGAUUCUCUGCUCCAUGUUUGGACAGGGUCGUGCCUGAUCUGAGAUAAAUGGACAAGAACAACUGAAGCCUGUCUUCUGGUGCAUGUGUCACCUGCCGAUAACUGCAUCUUGUGAUAAAGUUGGGUGAUUUACAGUCUCCACCAAAUGCUAAACUCUGGGGUCUUACGCCUUUAUAACUCCAUGGGCCCCAGCAAAGGUUCAGGCUCAAAACAGGUGUCAAAUAGAUAACUGUUGAAUGAUUGUUCCCCAGUUGCAGGCUCUGCCACCUGGCGUUCAUACUGUCUGUGAAAGGACCCAGCUCACCUUUCCCUCUUUAUCUCCCAGUCCUUCCCAACAGCGCCGACACCUCAUGGAAACUGAUUGCAAAUGUGCUACUUCUCACUUCUGUGUGGCCCGAGGAGGCUGGGUUAAUGCUGGGCUUGGUACCUUAAGCACCCUUUCUCCCUUCCCCAUCUUCAUUCUCAGAAUUACACCUGUCUGAAGCAGGCAUUUUCCAAUGCCCUAGAUGGGAAUAUAAGUGUAAGGAGAUGUGAAGCAUUUGCCUGUGUGUCAGAACAUUCACUGAGGAUCCUCAUAGGCACUUCUAGAAACCAAAUCCUUGAAGAUGACUAACCAGAAAUGCCCGUCAUAGCACUGUUUACAGUUGCAAAAACUGAAGCCAAUUGAAAUGUCCAUCAGGAGGGGAUUAAAUGAAUUAUGGUACAGUUACACCGUUGAAUAUUUUACAGCCAUUGAAGAUGAUAUAUAGCUAUAUUCAUUGACAAGGAAAACUCAUAUUUUUUAGUGAAAAAAGCAGGUUAUAGAAUUGCAUGAUAUUCACAUUUAUAUAAAACUUUAUAUAUGGGAAGGAUGUUGAUUGAAUUGUUAAUAACUAUGGUCACCUCUAGAGAUGGAAGUUUGCAUUACCUUUAAUUUUUAAUACCAUUUUGUAUUGCUUAAAAUUUGUAUGUAUUAUCGUUAAAAUAAGAAAAAUCAAAUAAAGCUAUUUUCAUUAUGGGAAAA